ACAAACGCUGAGCCCCGCCCCGCUGAGGCCUGUCUGCAGAAUCCACAGCAACCAGCACCAUGCCCAUGACACUGGGGUACUGGAACAUCCGCGGGCUGGCCCAUUCCAUCCGCCUGCUCCUGGAAUACACAGACUCAAGCUACGAGGAAAAGAAGUACACGAUGGGGGACGCUCCUGAUUAUGACAGAAGCCAGUGGCUGAAUGAAAAAUUCAAGCUGGGCCUGGACUUUCCCAAUCUGCCCUACUUGAUUGAUGGGACUCACAAGAUCACCCAGAGCAACGCCAUCCUGCGGUACAUUGCCCGCAAGCACAACCUGUGCGGGGAAUCAGAAAAGGAGCAGAUUCGCGAAGACAUUUUGGAGAACCAGUUUAUGGACAGCCGUAUGCAGCUGGCCAAACUCUGCUAUGACCCAGAUUUUGAGAAACUGAAACCAGAAUACCUGCAGGCACUCCCUGAAAUGCUGAAGCUCUACUCACAGUUUCUGGGGAAGCAGCCAUGGUUUCUUGGGGACAAGAUCACCUUUGUGGAUUUCAUCGCUUAUGAUGUCCUUGAGAGAAACCAAGUAUUUGAGCCCAGCUGCCUGGAUGCCUUCCCAAACCUGAAGGACUUCAUCUCCCGAUUUGAGCAUUCCUGAUGUUUGGAUUCAGGCUGCUUCCCUCAUCCCUGCUGCUCCUGAUCCCCGUCCACAGACCCACUUUCCCCGCUGGUGUGAUCCUUGUGGCCACUAUGGCAGCUACUUUGGAGAGCCGCUAGUCCAGUCCUUCCCGCCUUCCGCAGAGCUCUACUCCUGCUUCUGAAGAAGCCACCUGGGGCCUGGCCUUCUUCCUGGCUCCUCAGAGUCCUUGCAACAGCAGGCACUACUUCUCUCUCCUGCACUCAACCCCUCUCCCACUCCACUGCCUCUCAGUGUGCCAAAACACGAAGAUGUGUCCUGAUUUUCAAAAUCUCUCCCCUGAAGUUCCCACCUGAUAUGUAGUUGGAGAUGGGCAAAUACAGCGUCCUUGAAGCAUCAUUUUAUUCAUAGUGCCUGGAAUGUAGUAGGAUCUCGACAAUUGUUGUUUCAAUAAAGGAAUGACCAAAUAUAUUAAUACUGUAAAAAGUAAAGUAGAGGUUCCUCUUCAAAGAGACUUUUCUCCCCAUCUAAUUAAGAAUAAGUCGUAACUUCUCUUAGAAGCAAAAUUUAUUCAAAGACCGGUGCUGAUAUUCUGAAAUAUCUGCUAGCUGUAAUAAAGAAAUUAAUGUACUUUAUGUUCUUAACUCCCACAAUUUAGCCUAAAUACUUGCCCUGGCAUGCUUAUACUGAUCCAAACAAGCAUGAGGUCAUAGCCUGUUCCUCUUCCUUAUUUGAAGGUGUUUUUACCUUACUCAGCAUUCCACAAGUGAGUUCCCCCUUCCUUUGUUCUCCUCUGCCUCUGCCUCUUUUAAAAAGUUCUAAGUUGCUA